GUCAUUGACGCCAUGAGCGCGCUGCUGCGGCUGCUGCGCACGGGUGCCCCAGCCGCUGCGUGCCUGCGGUUGGGGACCAGUGCAGGGACCGGGUCGCGCCGUGCUAUGGCCCUGUACCACACUGAGGAGCGCGGCCAGCCCUGCUCGCAGAAUUACCGCCUCUUCUUUAAGAAUGUAACUGGUCACUACAUUUCCCCCUUUCAUGAUAUUCCUCUGAAGGUGAACUCUAAAGAGGAAAAUGGCAUUCCUAUGAAGAAAGCACGAAAUGAUGAAUAUGAGAAUCUGUUUAAUAUGAUUGUAGAAAUACCUCGGUGGACAAAUGCUAAAAUGGAGAUUGCCACCAAGGAGCCAAUGAAUCCCAUUAAACAAUAUGUAAAGGAUGGAAAGCUACGCUAUGUGGCGAAUAUCUUCCCUUACAAGGGUUAUAUAUGGAAUUAUGGUACCCUCCCUCAGACUUGGGAAGAUCCCCAUGAAAAAGAUAAGAGCACGAACUGCUUUGGAGAUAAUGAUCCUAUUGAUGUUUGCGAAAUAGGCUCAAAGAUUCUUUCUUGUGGAGAAGUUAUUCAUGUGAAGAUCCUUGGAAUUUUGGCUCUUAUUGAUGAAGGUGAAACAGAUUGGAAAUUAAUUGCUAUCAAUGCGAAUGAUCCUGAAGCCUCAAAGUUUCAUGAUAUUGAUGAUGUUAAGAAGUUCAAACCGGGUUACCUGGAAGCUACUCUUAAUUGGUUUAGAUUAUAUAAGGUACCAGAUGGAAAACCAGAAAACCAGUUUGCUUUUAAUGGAGAAUUCAAAAACAAGGCUUUUGCUCUUGAAGUUAUUAAAUCCACUCAUCAAUGUUGGAAAGCAUUGCUUAUGAAGAAGUGUAAUGGAGGAGCUAUAAAUUGCACAAACGUGCAGAUAUCUGAUAGCCCUUUCCGUUGCACUCAAGAGGAAGCAAGAUCAUUAGUUGAAUCGGUAUCAUCUUCACCAAAUAAAGAAAGUAAUGAAGAAGAGCAAGUGUGGCACUUCCUUGGCAAGUGAUUGAAACAUCUGAAAUUCUGCUGUCAAGAUUCCCAUCUCUAAGGACUCCAAGUGCUAGAGACAAGGGGGUCUAUGAGCAUUUACUGACUUCCUGUUAAAACUUCAUUUUUUCAAACUUUUUGAGCUAUGCAAUAUAUAAAUAAACAGUAAGAAUUUUAAAUUACUCUCCUUUGGACAUUUAUUGAUAUAAAAAGAAGAUUUUGGCCAGGCACGGUGGCUCAUGCCUGUAAUUUCAGCACUUUGGGAGGCCGAGGUGGGCAGAUCACAAGGUCAGGAGUUCAAGACCAGCCUGGCCAGUAUGUUGAAACCCCAUCUCUAUUAAAAAUACAAAAAUUAGCCAGGCGUGGUGGUGCAUGCCUGUAGACCCAGCUACUCAGGAGGCUGAGGCAGAAGAACUGCUUGAGCCCAGGAGGCAGAGGUUGCAGUGAGCAGAGAUUGUGCCACUGCACUCCAGCCUAGGCGACAGAGAGAGACUCCGUCUCAAAAAAAAAAAAAAGAUUUUGUUUCAUUUCAUAGCACAAAUUUAGAGGCAUUGAGUUGACCAUUUCUAGUUUCUAUACCUGAAGGAACCCAUUGAUUUUACCAGUUUUUAUUUCUGUAGAUUGGAUGUAAAAAUCACAGAUUCAAUAAAUUAAUAAACUUUGUGUA